CUCUCGCUUCCAGCUGUGGGUGGCGCUAGGCAGCUUCAGCCGGACCGGGUAGGGGUCCUCGCUCGCUAGCUUGCUGUUUCUCGGAGAAGCUCCCGAGUGUCCGGCCUAGAGGCCAUGAGAAGGCAGUGGGGGUCUGCCAUGAGGGCGGCCGAGCAGGCGGGCUGCAUGGUGAGCGCCUCCCGGGCCGGACAGCCCGAGGCGGGCCCGUGGAGCUGCAGCGGGGUAAUCCUGAGCCGUAGCCCGGGCCUGGUGCUUUGCCACGGGGGCAUCUUCGUCCCCUUCCUGCGAGCUGGCAGCGAAGUCCUGACCGCGGCCGGCGCCGUCUUCCUGCCUGGCGACAGUUGCAGGGACGACCUGCGCCUGCACGUGCAGUGGGCCCCAACGGCCGCGGGUCCCGGGGGCGGCGCGGAGCGGGGCCGCCCAGGGCUGUGCACGCCCCAGUGCGCGAGCCUCGAGCCCGGCCCACCUGCCCCGUCCCGCGGGCGUCCCCUGCAGCCCCGGCUUCCUGCUGAGCUGCUGCUGCUGCUGAGCUGCCCGGCCUUCUGGGCCCACUUCGCGCGCCUCUUCGGGGACGAGGCAGCGGAACAGUGGCGCUUCUCGAGCGCGGCGCGGGAUGACGAAGUGUCGGAGGACGAGGAGGCGGAUCAACUGAGAGCGCUGGGCUGGUUUGCGCUGCUGGGCGUGCGGCUAGGCCAGGAGGAGGUGGAGGAGGAGCGCGGGCCAGCCAUGGCGGUGUCGCCUCUCGGGGCCGUGCCCAAGGGUGCGCCAUUGCUGGUCUGCGGCUCCCCUUUCGGCGCCUUCUGCCCCGACAUCUUUCUCAACACGCUGAGCUGCGGGGUGCUCAGCAACGUGGCCGGCCCACUGCUGCUUACCGACGCACGCUGCCUGCCCGGCACCGAGGGCGGCGGCGUGUUCACCGCGCGGCCCGCGGGGGCGCUGGUGGCGCUGGUGGUGGCGCCGCUCUGUUGGAAGGCCGGCGAAUGGGUGGGCUUCACGCUGCUCUGCGCCGCCGCCCCCCUUUUCCGCGCCGCCCGCGACGCGCUUCACCGCCUGCCGCACAGCACCGCUGCCCUGGCCGCCCUUCUGCCGCCAGAGGUGGGCGUCCCGUGGGGUCUGCCCCUCCGAGACUCCGGGCCCCUGUGGGCAGCCGCGGCAGUGUUGGUGGAGUGCGGCACCGUAUGGGGCUCCGGAGUGGCUGUGGCACCCCGCCUUGUAGUGACCUGUCGGCACGUGUCCCCUCGGGAAGCAGCCAGGGUCCUGGUGCGCUCCACCACCCCCAAGAGUGUGGCCAUCUGGGGCCGUGUGGUAUUUGCCACUCAGGAGACAUGUCCCUAUGACAUAGCAGUGGUGAGCCUGGAGGAGGACCUGGAUGAUGUCCCCAUCCCUGUGCCCGCUGAGCACUUCCAUGAAGGCGAGGCUGUGAGUGUGGUGGGCUUUGGCGUCUUUGGCCAGUCUUGCGGGCCCUCGGUGACCUCAGGCAUCCUUUCGGCUGUGGUGCAGGUGAAUGGCACGCCCGUAAUGCUGCAGACCACGUGUGCUGUGCACAGCGGCUCCAGUGGGGGACCCCUCUUCUCCAACCACUCAGGAAACCUCCUUGGCAUAAUCACCAGCAACACCCGGGACAAUAAUACGGGGGCCACCUACCCCCACCUGAACUUCAGCAUUCCCAUCACGGUGCUCCAGCCGGCCCUGCAGCAGUACAGCCAGACCCAAGACCUAGGUGGCCUCCGUGAGCUGGACCGCGCUGCUGAGCCAGUCAGGGUGGUGUGGCGGUUGCAGCGGCCCCUGGCAGAGGCCCCGCGGAGCAAGCUCUGAGGCUGUGUUACCACCUUUGGAAAGAAGAGUGACCUUUUUCUGCUGUAGGAAGUGAUGUUGAGGUGACGGUGGCCUCAGGAUUCAGGGCCCAGCCCCUGCAGGGGCCCAGGCUGCCUCUCAUCUCCACCCACUGACUGCAGACUGGGCUUUGGGCUCUGGGGCAAACUUCUCUUCAGCCCCAUGGAUCCUUAACCUGGCAGCCCGUUUUGGGGUGCUUUCUUGAGCCCCCAGUUCUCUGUCCCCUAGCACUAGACUCAGCUGUAUUGUUUUUCCUUCUGGGGAGCCCACUCCAACUGCACAGAAGUUCUGGGCCUGACAGGUAGAUUCCAGCUGGAAGGCAGGCCCGUGCCUGGUUUUGCGUCUGUUCCCCUGAGGGCCAUCGUCAUCCUGGAGCUUCAAUGGGGCCUUGGCUCCUGUCUGCCUCUCAGUCAGAGUCAGGGCUGACAAAGGACUCAGCUUCCUUAGCAUCUCAGCAGAAACCUUGCUCUGAAGACCAGAGACAGAAGGGACAGAAACAGGAGUGCCUCCUGCUGUGCCAGGCCCAUGGGCAGUGCAGGCAGAUCCCUGAAGGUCAGCACUCCUGGGUCUUCAUAUGCCAACAGGGGCGCUCUUGACACUGUGCCUUCAUUUUCCAGCCCACAGCCUGGGUCUCAGGGAUCUUGAGGGGUAGAACAUGUCUGGUUGGGGCUUGGGAAUAAACAUGAUCUAUUGAAAAACCUCUGUAUUUAUAUAUCAAAUUGUUUCUUUUUUUCAGGAGUUGAACUGGGAAUAGGCAAGUACCAGGCAAAGAAACACACCCUUUCCUUUUUUUUUUUUUUUUUUCUUUAGAGCUGUGGUCUUGCUCUCUCACCCAGGCUGGAGUGCAGUGUUGCGAUCACAGCUCACUGCAGCCUCAAACUCCUGGGCUCCAGGAGACCUCCUGCCUCAGCCUCCUGAAUAGCUGGGACUACAGUCGCGCACCACCACGCCUGGCUAAUUUUUUAUUUUUGUAGAAAUGGGGUAUUGCUUUGUUGCCCGUGCUGGCUUCAGCCUUCUGGUUUCAAGCAGUCCUCCUGCCUCAGCUUCCCAAAGUGCUGGGAUUACAGGUGUGAGCCACUGUGCCCAACCCAGAAAUACACCCUUUCUGUGCUGUUUUCUCAGCAGGGUGUGAGCUCACGGGAUACGGUCCUGCCAGACUGGCCCUCAUAGCUGGUCAUGUGCCAGUCAGAGCUGGGUGGGGCUUGCAGGUCCCGGAAGGUGGUGGUCUUGACCUGGCAGCAGAUGCUUAAAGAAUGCCUAAGGUGGGUGGCAGUUGGGGAGUUCAAGGGUGAAUGAGGCCAGGGCAGCCCCCAGGAGCUGAGGCCAACUCUUUGAGUCAGGACUGUGCCGUGUGCCCAGGGCCUUGCAUGUGUGGGCCCUCGAGUGAUUUCUACUGGCAGGCUGAAAGCCCUGUGAGGGGCGGCUGUGGGCGGAGGCCACGCAGGAAGAGUGCUUAGGAGUAACUUGUUUCUAACACCUGUGUGCUGAGUGCCAAUGCUGGGUGUGGUGUUAUGAUAUAUAUUGGUUUUCAUCCAGCAUUCCUGACUCGUAACUCUCAUAGUCCUUGUUCCAGUCUUUGUUAGAAUACUGGGUAUGUUAGGGCUUGGGACAGGCCUCUGACCUCUGGGUAUCCUUUCACUAAUGUUCGCCCACCUUUUUCACAGUGGGUCCUAAAGACCUUCCCAUGAGAGGGUCUCAAUCCUAGGGGAAGGAAUGUUGAUGUCAUGAACCUUCCAUAAAAACCCAAGAGGACAGGGUUCAGAGAGCUUCUGGAUAGCUGAACACCUGGCACUUCCUGGAGUGUGGCGUGCCCAGGGAGGGCACGGAAGCUCUGCACUCCUUCCCCUUCCCUCAUUCCUUGCUCUAUGUGCAUCUCUUCAUCUGUAUCCUUUGCGAUAUCCUUUAUAAUAAACCGGUAAACAUAA